CUUCCCCCUUCCUUUUCUUCUUCCCUUUGAUGAAAAGCUUCCCUUUCAUGACGUAUAGCUGGCAGCAAACUUAAAGUUGCUGUGCGUCUGAAAUACAGGAAUGGGAAAGAAACUCCGACCAAGCAUAAAACACACUCAUUUUCUAGAGCUCAGUCAUUUGCUAAGGGUUGAAAUAAACUGUGCACCCCCACUCCCUGCCCCUUCCCCCUGGCUCCUUGGCCUUUUUGUCACCGGACUGGAUUCUGAAGGACGUCCAGGUAAUGCUGGGUUUCAGCAGCUGAAAGCCCUGGCAGAAGGGAUUGCAGGUUUCACAUUCUUCCUUCUCUUGGUAUUCAAAACUUUAUUUUUUUUUUUGCGAGAUAGAAAUUCUUGAUAGAGAGCUUCCAGACUGCUGGUGGCAGGGAAGAAAUCUGGUUAAGAGAUUCAGAAAGCAGAAAAUUCUUUUUCUCUGCGCAAGCAGUCCACAACAGCAUUUAGCUAGGAUUUAUAAGAUUCUUGGUGGAGCAAGGGGAGGCACAUCGACAAAGGAGAGUUUAUAUAAGCCACUGGCUUUGAGCUACAUUGAAAAAAUAUGUAUGGCAGCCACGUUUUCUUAGUGGGAAAGAAAAUUAUUCAGGGAAUGAAAUUUUGAAGGCUAAUUCUCUCCAAGAAUCUUGCUUCACAUAAUUUAAAGGAGGUGUCAUCCCUGUAUUUGUUCACUGAAGAGUCCACGAACUUUAAUUAGUCACCUACUGUGCCAGACAAUGUGAUAAAUGGUGUAAUUGAACAUAAUGGAGAGAGGAAUUAAUUUUUGUUAAGAGGUUGAGAAGAGGUUCAUAAAGGAGAGAGAGGUCUGUGGCUUUAAAAAUAGUCAUUCCUAGUCAGUGGCUAGCCAAGAAAUGUAUCUGGAAGGUCAUGCCCUGUACAGAAUAAGUAAGGAAGGGCAUGAGGGCUUGAUGUCUUGUUACAAAGUUUAGAGGUAUAUGUGUGUUUUGUAGACCUAGAACAUCUUUGAAUAUUUUUUUCCAGCAAAUUCGUUAAAGUAACAACAACAAAAUAGCCUGAGAAAAUUGGGCAAUAGAUAGCACACAGUAGAAAUAUUAUUGUUGUUUGCAUUUAAAUGAAGAAUUGAAUACAUUGAUGUAUUACAGUAGAGAGUGGAAGCAAAUAUGUUAAGAAGAUAAUGUAACAUCCAGAAAAGAGGACUAAUGAAAGAAUAGGGCCUAAAGCUAAUCAGUAUAACUAAGAAAGAAAAGAAGGCUACUUUGGGGAAUAAAAUUUCUCUUUAGGCAUCAUCAUCUAUCCACUCAGAUCUUUUUACUCAUCUCAGUUUCCCCAUCCAGCCUUCGAAAAAUUCCCCAUCUUCCAUCUAUCGAGUAAACUCCGUUUGUCCUGGGGAGACCCCCACUCCUUCAGCCACUUUCAAGCACAUUCAUCUUCACCUCACCCCAUUUUCUACACACAUCCCUGCAUCAUCUCUGAACCUUACAUCAUGUAACAUUUUACCCACUUCAGCCUUCUUUCUACAACCAGUUAGAGCCUCUUAAUCUUGUCUUUUUCCUCCCUUUAGGCACUAACAAAUAGCUCUAUCUCGCUUCUUUUUCCUCCUCUAAGUCAGCUAUUCCCCGCCCCUUUCCCAUGCAUUAAUUAUCCUGCUAAUUUGUCCACUCAUUUCCCCCUUUUACAUCCUCCUCCCCAUUAGCCACCUUGCAUUCUCCUAUCUUUCAUUGACCUCAAAGAAGCUAAGGGGAAAGAAAAGCCACUCUACUUUAAACUUGCUUAGAUUUGCCAAAUUUUCGUCAUCAAGGUUUCUUCCUUUCUGUGUCUUUUGCUGUUUUAGUUCACACAAGACUUUUAGUGGAAUUCCUUCAAUUUGUUAUAUAUUUUUAUUAUGCCUGCAAAUGUCUGUUUUCCUUUGGUUGUGGCUGGGGAUUCAAAUAUUUUACUUUGGGGAGUAUUUCCAACCUUUCUGAAGUUCUCACUGACACACUCCUGACACUGUUUCGCUGCAUCCCAUCCUUUCUGCUGUAUUCUCUUCCCAUGGGUAAUUCCUUUUAUAUUUUCAGUGAAAUUCUUUCUUAUUUUUAUUCCCUCCUCCCCCCCUCCUCCUUUUUUUCUUUUUGCUUUGUGGGAUUGGUAUAGCGGCUCAAGUUUAAAUAUUUUGAGAAGGGACCCCCCUCAGCAGACCCCCUCAUCCCACACACAGGAUUUUAAAGCCUGUGUCAACGUGUGUUCAUGUCAACAUACAGUUACCAAUCUUCAGAGGCAAAGGAACCCCUGUUUGUUUUAUUUUAACUGCACUCUUAGAAAAUUCUUUUUCUGUGUGUAUGGUAAAGGUGCAAUUCUCAUAUCGUUCUUCUCUCUACAUUCAGUGGAAUUGAUUCAACAUCGCUGGGAAUUGGGAAGGGAAGAAAGAGUACGCUGUAAAAAUACAUUUUUCAUCAAAGACAUAUAUACAUAUUACCUUUGGGAAAAAUAAAAUACUUUGGAACAUUUAAUUGGAUUGGCUUUAUAUGACAACAUUCCAAAUUACAUGUCAUUGUCUGAGCAGAGUUCUAUUAUUUGAAGACUUUAUUGAUCAUUCAGUGUCCAGAAUGAAGAAAACUAGAGGGUGCUUAAAAAGUACAGAUCAACUGGAUGGAUGAAUGGAUGGAAGAGGAUGGAAUAUCUUAACAAAACACAUUUUCCUUAAGUAAAUUCAUGCAUACUCCAAAUAAAAUACAGAAUGUGAAGUAUCUCUGAACUGUGCUGUUGAAUAUGGUAGCUACUAGCUACAUGAAAAUCCUGUUGCGAAUAAGAAGGAUUCCACAGAUCACAUACCGGAGAGGUUUUGCCUCAGCUGCUCUCAACUUUGUAAUCUUGUGAAGAAGCUGACAAGCUUGGCUGAUUGCAGAGCACUAUGAGGACUGAACGACAGUGGGUUUUAAUUCAGAUAUUUCAAGUGUUGUGCGGGUUAAUACAACAAACUGUAACAAGUGUACCUGGUAUGGACUUGUUGUCCGGGACGUACAUUUUCGCGGUCCUGCUAGCAUGCGUGGUGUUCCACUCUGGCGCCCAGGAGAAAAACUACACCAUCCGAGAAGAAAUGCCAGAAAACGUCCUGAUAGGCGACUUGUUGAAAGACCUUAACUUGUCGCUGAUUCCAAACAAGUCCUUGACAACUGCUAUGCAGUUCAAGCUAGUGUACAAGACCGGAGAUGUGCCACUGAUUCGAAUUGAAGAGGAUACUGGUGAGAUCUUCACUACUGGCGCUCGCAUUGAUCGUGAGAAAUUAUGUGCUGGUAUCCCAAGGGAUGAGCAUUGCUUUUAUGAAGUGGAGGUUGCCAUUUUGCCGGAUGAAAUAUUUAGACUGGUUAAGAUACGUUUUCUGAUAGAAGAUAUAAAUGAUAAUGCACCAUUGUUCCCAGCAACAGUUAUCAACAUAUCAAUUCCAGAGAACUCGGCUAUAAACUCUAAAUAUACUCUCCCAGCGGCUGUUGAUCCUGACGUAGGAAUAAACGGAGUUCAAAACUACGAACUAAUUAAGAGUCAAAACAUUUUUGGCCUCGAUGUCAUUGAAACACCAGAAGGAGACAAGAUGCCACAACUGAUUGUUCAAAAGGAGUUAGAUAGGGAAGAGAAGGAUACCUACGUGAUGAAAGUAAAGGUUGAAGAUGGUGGCUUUCCUCAAAGAUCCAGUACUGCUAUUUUGCAAGUGAGUGUUACUGAUACAAAUGACAACCACCCAGUCUUUAAGGAGACAGAGAUUGAAGUCAGUAUACCAGAAAAUGCUCCUGUAGGCACUUCAGUGACACAGCUCCAUGCCACAGAUGCUGACAUAGGUGAAAAUGCCAAGAUCCACUUCUCUUUCAGCAAUCUAGUCUCCAACAUUGCCAGGAGAUUAUUUCACCUCAAUGCCACCACUGGACUUAUCACAAUCAAAGAACCACUGGAUAGGGAAGAAACACCAAACCACAAGUUACUGGUUUUGGCAAGUGAUGGUGGAUUGAUGCCAGCAAGAGCAAUGGUGCUGGUAAAUGUUACAGAUGUCAAUGAUAAUGUCCCAUCCAUUGACAUAAGAUACAUCGUCAAUCCUGUCAAUGACACAGUUGUUCUUUCAGAAAAUAUUCCACUCAACACCAAAAUUGCUCUCAUAACUGUGACGGAUAAGGAUGCGGACCAUAAUGGCAGGGUGACAUGCUUCACAGAUCAUGAAAUCCCUUUCAGAUUAAGGCCAGUAUUCAGUAAUCAGUUCCUCCUGGAGACUGCAGCAUAUCUUGACUAUGAGUCCACAAAAGAAUAUGCCAUUAAAUUACUGGCUGCAGAUGCUGGCAAACCUCCUUUGAAUCAGUCAGCAAUGCUCUUCAUCAAAGUGAAAGAUGAAAAUGACAAUGCUCCAGUUUUCACCCAGUCUUUCGUAACUGUUUCUAUUCCUGAGAAUAACUCUCCUGGCAUCCAGUUGACGAAAGUAAGUGCAAUGGAUGCAGACAGUGGGCCUAAUGCUAAGAUCAAUUACCUGCUAGGCCCUGAUGCUCCACCUGAAUUCAGCCUGGAUUGUCGUACAGGCAUGCUGACUGUAGUGAAGAAACUAGAUAGAGAAAAAGAGGAUAAAUAUUUAUUCACAAUUCUGGCAAAAGAUAACGGGGUACCACCCUUAACCAGCAAUGUCACAGUCUUUGUAAGCAUUAUUGAUCAGAAUGACAAUAGCCCAGUUUUCACUCACAAUGAAUACAACUUCUAUGUCCCAGAAAACCUUCCAAGGCAUGGUACAGUAGGACUAAUCACUGUAACUGAUCCUGAUUAUGGAGACAAUUCUGCAGUUACGCUCUCCAUUUUAGAUGAGAAUGAUGACUUCACCAUUGAUUCACAAACUGGUGUCAUCCGACCAAAUAUUUCAUUUGAUAGAGAAAAACAAGAAUCUUACACUUUCUAUGUAAAGGCUGAGGAUGGUGGUAGAGUAUCACGUUCUUCAAGUGCCAAAGUAACCAUAAAUGUGGUUGAUGUCAAUGACAACAAACCAGUUUUCAUUGUCCCUCCUUCCAACUGUUCUUAUGAAUUGGUUCUACCGUCCACUAAUCCAGGCACAGUGGUCUUUCAGGUAAUUGCUGUUGACAAUGACACUGGCAUGAAUGCAGAGGUUCGUUACAGCAUUGUAGGAGGAAACACAAGAGAUCUGUUUGCAAUCGACCAAGAAACAGGCAACAUAACAUUGAUGGAGAAAUGUGAUGUUACAGACCUUGGUUUACACAGAGUGUUGGUCAAAGCUAAUGACUUAGGACAGCCUGAUUCUCUCUUCAGUGUUGUAAUUGUCAAUCUGUUCGUGAAUGAGUCGGUGACCAAUGCUACACUGAUUAAUGAACUGGUGCGCAAAAGCACUGAAGCACCAGUGACCCCAAAUACUGAGAUAGCUGAUGUAUCCUCACCAACUAGUGACUAUGUCAAGAUCCUGGUUGCAGCUGUUGCUGGCACCAUAACUGUCGUUGUAGUUAUUUUCAUCACUGCUGUAGUAAGAUGUCGCCAGGCACCACACCUUAAGGCUGCUCAGAAAAACAAGCAGAAUUCUGAAUGGGCUACCCCAAACCCAGAAAACAGGCAGAUGAUAAUGAUGAAGAAAAAGAAAAAGAAGAAGAAGCAUUCCCCUAAGAACUUGCUGCUUAAUUUUGUCACUAUUGAAGAAACUAAGGCAGAUGAUGUUGACAGUGAUGGAAACAGAGUCACACUAGACCUUCCUAUUGAUCUAGAAGAGCAAACAAUGGGAAAGUACAAUUGGGUAACUACACCUACUACUUUCAAGCCCGACAGCCCUGAUUUGGCCCGACACUACAAAUCUGCCUCUCCACAGCCUGCCUUCCAAAUUCAGCCUGAAACUCCCCUGAAUUCGAAGCACCACAUCAUCCAAGAACUGCCUCUCGAUAACACCUUUGUGGCCUGUGACUCUAUCUCCAAGUGUUCCUCAAGCAGUUCAGAUCCCUACAGCGUUUCUGACUGUGGCUAUCCAGUGACGACCUUCGAGGUACCUGUGUCCGUACACACCAGACCGCCAAUGAAGGAGGUUGUGCGAUCUUGCACCCCCAUGAAAGAGUCUACAACUAUGGAGAUCUGGAUUCAUCCCCAACCACAGCGGAAAUCUGAAGGGAAAGUGGCAGGAAAGUCCCAGCGGCGUGUCACAUUUCACCUGCCAGAAGGCUCUCAGGAAAGCAGCAGUGAUGGUGGACUGGGAGACCAUGAUGCAGGCAGCCUUACCAGCACAUCUCAUGGCCUGCCCCUUGGCUAUCCUCAGGAGGAGUACUUUGAUCGUGCUACACCCAGCAAUCGCACUGAAGGGGAUGGCAACUCCGAUCCUGAAUCUACUGCAGAAAUAACUGUUCAACCAACUGUGGAAGAGGCCUCUGACAACUGCACUCAAGAAUGUCUCAUCUAUGGCCAUUCUGAUGCCUGCUGGAUGCCGGCAUCUCUGGAUCAUUCCAGCUCUUCGCAAGCACAGGCCUCUGCUCUAUGCCACAGCCCACCACUGUCACAGGCCUCUACUCAGCACCACAGCCCACGAGUGACACAGACCAUUGCUCUCUGCCACAGCCCUCCAGUGACACAGACCAUCGCAUUGUGCCACAGCCCACCACCGAUACAGGUGUCUGCUCUCCACCACAGUCCUCCUCUAGUGCAGGCUACUGCACUUCACCACAGCCCACCAUCAGCACAGGCCUCAGCCCUCUGCUACAGCCCUCCUUUAGCACAGGCUGCUGCAAUCAGCCACAGCUCUCCUCUGCCACAGGUUAUUGCCCUCCAUCGUAGUCAGGCCCAAUCAUCAGUCAGUUUGCAGCAAGGUUGGGUGCAAGGUGCUGAUGGGCUAUGCUCUGUUGAUCAGGGAGUGCAAGGUAGUGCAACAUCUCAGUUUUACACCAUGUCUGAAAGACUUCAUCCCAGUGAUGAUUCAAUUAAAGUCAUUCCUUUGACAACCUUCACUCCACGCCAACAGGCCAGACCGUCCAGAGGUGAUUCCCCCAUUAUGGAAGAACAUCCCUUGUAAAGCUAAAAUAGUUACUUCAAAUUUUCAGAAAAGAUGUAUAUAGUCAAAAUUUAAGAUACAAUUCCAAUGAGUAUUCUGAUUAUCAGAUUUGUAAAUAACUAUGUAAAUAGAAACAGAUACCAGAAUAAAUCUACAGCUAGACCCUUAGUCAAUAGUUAACCAAAAAAUUGCAAUUUGUUUAAUUCAGAAUGUGUAUUUAAAAAGAAAAGGAAUUUAACAAUUUGCAUCCCCUUGUACAGUAAGGCUUAUCAUGACAGAGCGCACUAUUUCUGAUGUACAGUAUUUUUUGUUGUUUUUAUCAUCAUGUGCAAUAUUACUGAUUUGUUUCCAUGCUGAUUGUGUGGAACCAGUAUGUAGCAAAUGGAAAGCCUAGAAAUAUCUUAUUUUCUAAGUUUACCUUUAGUUUACCUAAACUUUUGUUCAGAUAACGUUAAAAGGUAUACGUACUCUAGCCUUUUUUUGGGCUUUCUUUUUGAUUUUUGUUUGUUGUUUUCAGUUUUUUUGUUGUUGUUAGUGAGUCUCCCUUCAAAAUACGCAGUAGGUAGUGUAAAUACUGCUUGUUUGUGUCUCUCUGCUGUCAUGUUUUCUACCUUAUUCCAAUACUAUAUUGUUGAUAAAAUUUGUAUAUACAUUUUCAAUAAAGAAUAUGUAUAAACUGUACAGAUCUAGAUCUACAACCUAUUUCUCUACUCUUUAGUAGAGUUCGAGACACAGAAGUGCAAUAACUGCCCUAAUUAAGCAACUAUUUGUUAAAAAGGGCCUCUUUUUACUUUAAUAGUUUAGUGUAAAGUACAUCAGAAAUAAAGCUGUAUCUGCCAUUUUAAGCCUGUAGUCCAUUAUUACUUGGGUCUUUACUUCUGGGAAUUUGUAUGUAACAGCCUAGAAAAUUAAAAGGAGGUGGAUGCAUCCAAAGCACGAGUCACUUAAAAUAUCGACGGUAAACUACUAUUUUGUAGAGAAACUCAGGAAGAUUUAAAUGUUGAUUUGACAGCUCAAUAGGCUGUUACCAAAGGGUGUUCAGUAAAAAUAACAAAUACAUGUAACUGUAGAUAAAACCAUAUACUAAAUCUAUAAGACUAAGGGAUUUUUGUUAUUCUAGCUCAACUUACUGAAGAAAACCACUAAUAACAACAAGAAUAUCAGGAAGGAACUUUUCAAGAAAUGUAAUUAUAAAUCUACAUCAAACAGAAUUUUAAGGAAAAAUGCAGAGGGAGAAAUAAGGCACAUGACUGCUUCUUGCAGUCAACAAGAAAUACCAAUAACACACACAGAACAAAAACCAUCAAAAUCUCAUAUAUGAAAUAAAAUAUAUUCUUCUAAGCAAAGAAACAGUACUAUUCAUAGAAAACAUUAGUUUUCUUCUGUUGUCUGUUAUUUCCUUCUUGUAUCCUCUUAACUGGCCAUUAUCUUGUAUGUGCACAUUUUAUAAAUGUACAGAAACAUCACCAACUUAAUUUUCUUCCAUAGCAAAACUGAGAAAAUACCUUGUUUCAGUAUAACACUAAACCAAGAGACAAUUGAUGUUUAAUGGGGGCGGUUGGGGUGGGGGGGGGAGUCAAUAUCUCCUAUUGAUUAACUUAGACAUAGAUUUUGUAAUGUAUAACUUGAUAUUUAAUUUAUGAUUAAACUGUGUGUAAAUUUUGUAACAUAAACUGUGGUAAUUGCAUAAUUUCAUUGGUGAGGAUUUCCACUGAAUAUUGAGAAAGUUUCUUUUCAUGUGCCCAGCAGGUUAAGUAGCGUUUUCAGAAUAUACAUUAUUCCCAUCCAUUGUAAAGUUCCUUAAGUCAUAUUUGACUGGGCGUGCAGAAUAACUUCUUAACUUUUAACUAUCAGAGUUUGAUUAAUAAAAUUAAUUAAUGUUUUUUCUCCUUCGUGUUGUUAAUGUUCCAAGGGAUUUGGAGCAUACUGGUUUUCCAGGUGCAUGUGAAUCCCGAAGGACUGAUGAUAUUUGAAUGUUUAUUAAAUUAUUAUCAUACAAAUGUGUUGAUAUUGUGGCUAUUGUUGAUGUUGAAAAUUUUAAACUUGGGGAAGAUUAAGAAAAGAACCAAUAGUGACAAAAAUCAGUGCUUCCAGUAGAUUUUAGAACAUUCUUUGCCUCAAAAAACCUGCAAAGAUGAUGUGAGAUUUUUUCUUGUGUUUUAAUUAUUUUCACAUUUUCUCUCUGCAAAACUUUAGUUUUCUGAUGAUCUACACACACACACACACACACACGUGCACACACACACACAUUUAAAUGAUAUAAAAAGAAGAGGUUGAAAGAUUAUUAAAUAACUUAUCAGGCAUCUCAAUGGUUACUAUCUAUGUUAGUGAAAAUCAAAUAGGACUCAAAGUUGGAUAUUUGGGAUUUUUCUUCUGACAGUAUAAUUUAUUGAGUUACUAGGGAGGUUCUUAAAUCCUCAUAUCUGGAAACUUGUGACGUUUUGACACCUUUCCUAUAGAUGAUAUAGGAAUGAACCAAUACGCUUUUAUUACCCUUUCUAACUCUGAUUUUAUAAUCAGACUUAGAUUGUGUUUAGAAUAUUAAAUGACUGGGCACCCUCUUCUUGGUUUUUACCAGAGAGGCUUUGAAUGGAAGCAGGCUGAGAGUAGCCAAAGAGGCAAGGGGUAUUAGCCCAGUUAUUCUCCCCUAUGCCUUCCUUCUCUUUCUAAGCGUCCACUAGGUCUGGCCUUGGAAACCUGUUACUUCUAGGGCUUCAGAUCUGAUGAUAUCUUUUUCAUCACAUUACAAGUUAUUUCUCUGACUGAAUAGACAGUGGUAUAGGUUGACACAGCACACAAGUGGCUAUUGUGAUGUAUGAUGUAUGUAGUCCUACAACUGCAAAACGUCUUACUGAACCAACAAUCAAAAAAUGGUUCUGUUUUAAAAAGGAUUUUGUUUGAUUUGAAAUUAAAACUUCAAGCUGAAUGACUUAUAUGAGAAUAAUACGUUCAAUCAAAGUAGUUAUUCUAUUUUGUGUCCAUAUUCCAUUAGAUUGUGAUUAUUAAUUUUCUAGCUAUGGUAUUACUAUAUCACACUUGUGAGUAUGUAUUCAAAUACUAAGUAUCUUAUAUGCUACGUGCAUACACAUUCUUUUCUUAAACUUUACCUGUGUUUUAACUAAUAUUGUGUCAGUGUAUUAAAAAUUAGCUUUUACAUAUGAUAUCUACAAUGUAAUAAAUUUAGAGAGUAAUUUUGUGUAUUCUUAUUUACUUAACAUUUUACUUUUAAUUAUGUAAAUUUGGUUAGAAAAUAAUAAUAAAUGGUUAGUGCUAUUGUGUAAUGGUAGCAGUUACAAAGAGCCUCUGCCUUCCCAAACUAAUAUUUAUCACACAUGGUCAUUAAAUGGGAAAAAAAUAGACUAAACAAAUCACAAAUUGUUCAGUUCUUAAAAUGUAAUUAUGUCACACACACAAAAAAUCCUUUUCAAUCCUGAGAAAAUUAAAGGCGUUUUACUCACAUGGCUAUUUCAACAUUAGUUUUUUUUGUUUGUUUCUUUUUCAUGGUAUUACUGAAGGUGUGUAUACUCCCUAAUACACAUUUAUGAAAAUCUACUUGUUUAGGCUUUUAUUUAUACUCUUCUGAUUUAUAUUUUUUAUUAUAAUUAUUAUUUCUUAUCUUUCUUCUUUUAUAUUUUUUGGAAACCAAAUUUAUAGUUAGUUUAGGUAAACUUUUUAUUAUGACCAUUAGAAACUAUUUUGAAUGCUUCCAACUGGCUCAAUUGGCCGGGAAAACAUGGGAGCAAGAGAAGCUGAAAUAUAUUUCUGCAAGAACCUUUCUAUAUUAUGUGCCAAUUACCACACCAGAUCAAUUUUAUGCAGAGGCCUUAAAAUAUUCUUUCACAGUAGCUUUCUUACACUAACCGUCAUGUGCUUUUAGUAAAUAUGAUUUUUAAAAGCAGUUCAAGUUGACAACAGCAGAAACAGUAACAAAAAAAUCUGCUCAGAAAAAUGUAUGUGCACAAAUAAAAAAAAUUAAUGGCAAUUGUUUAGUGAUUGUAAGUGAUACUUUUUAAAGAGUAAACUGUGUGAAAUUUAUACUAUCCCUGCUUAAAAUAUUAAGAUUUUUAUGAAAUAUGUAUUUAUGUUUGUAUUGUGGGAAGAUUCCUCCUCUGUGAUAUCAUACAGCAUCUGAAAGUGAACAGUAUCCCAAAGCAGUUCCAACCAUGCUUUGGAAGUAAGAAGGUUGACUAUUGUAUGGCCAAGGAUGGCAGUAUGUAAUCCAGAAGCAAACUUGUAUUAAUUGUUCUAUUUCAGGUUCUGUAUUGCAUGUUUUCUUAUUAAUAUAUAUUAAUAAAAGUUAUGAGAAAUAAA